GUGGACUGGGGCCGGAUAAUGGCGGGCGCUGCAGAAGAUGCGCGAGCUCUUUUCCGGGCUGGGGUCUGCGCGGCCCUGGAGGCCUGGCCGGCCUUGCAGAUCGCUGUGGAGAAUGGCUUCGGGGGUGUGCACAGCCAGGAGAAGGCCAAGUGGCUGGGGGGUGCAGUGGAGGAUUACUUCAUGCGCAAUGGUGAGUGAAUGUGAGGCGCCGCGACCCGCCUGUGUGGGGGUGUGGAGAGGAGGAGCCCCAUCCCGCAGAGCCUGCAUUUCCUCUCGAGCAGUUGUGGAUUGGUACCUAAAGCUGACUUGGAGCUAGAUGAGGUGGAAGACUUCCUUGGAGAGCUGUUGACCAACGAGUUUGAUACAGUUGUGGAAGACGGGAGUCUGCCCCAGGUGAGCCAGCAACUGCAGACCAUGUUCCACCACUUCCAGAGGGGUGAUGGGGCUGCUCUGAGGGAGAUGGCCUCCUGCAUCACUCAGAGAAAAUGCAAGGUCACAGCCACUGCACUUAAGACAGCUAGAGAGACUGAUGAGGAUGAAGAUGAUGUGGACAGUGUGGAAGAGAUGGAGGUCACAGCUACGAAUGAUGGGGCUGCUACAGAUGGGGUCUGCCCCCAGCCUGAACCCUCUGAUCCAGACGCUCAGACUAUUAAGGAAGAGGAUAUAGUGGAAGAUGGCUGGACCAUUGUCCGGAGAAAAAAAUGAGUGGGGAUGAUUGGAAAUGGCUUUGGGCCCUUAUUUGCUGUUCUAAGAGUUGUCUGUAGGGGUUUUUUUUUUGAGGAUUGCAGACCUGUGGACUGGUUACCCCAUCUCCACCCUCUCCCCUGUUCCUCUGUCUGGCUCCCUCCAGGGCAAGGAAAACCUAGGGUCCUUGGUCUUGGGGGUGGGGGGACCUUUUCCAGCAUAUUCCCCUGGGCCUUUAGUUAACAUCCGAGUGACGAAGCCGGGUUCCCCAGUACAGUGUCUUUUGGGUGCGGUCAUUGUGAGGAAGGGGAUGAGUGAGUGUGGGUGUGGCUGGAGGAGGAGCUAGAUGCCGGUGGACAGUGGGCAGGUGGAUUUGGGGAGGAGAGGAUCAGCAGCAGCAGCAGUACUCAGUGAUAGGGGGCUGGCUGGGUCAGGAAUGGUGAGAUGAACAUGCAAGUGGAAGAGAGAAUAGUUGAAAAUGUGAAUGAAAGUAGCUCUGGAGCCUCUCCCUUACCCCACCCCACACACACGCAACAGCUCUGUACCCCUGCCCAGAACUUGGAACCUCCCAGGAAUGCUGCCUUCCUUCAGCCCAGCCUCCAGUCCUGGGUUCCCUCAGGAAUUCGAAGACCUUGGCUAGGUGGUGAGCUUGGAAGAGCUGGGCUUUGUUUUCUGUCUCCUCUAACCUCUUUCCUUACUCCUUAUCCCAUCCCAUUUGAGUUCAGGGGUGAGGCUUAAGAUCUUAAUAAAUAAUACCUUACUGCUUAAUCUGUGGCUUGACCUGUGAGUAGUAGCCUUAGAAUCAGCCUUCUGGGAGCUCAGCUUCAGAGUUUACAAGGGAGCAGUUUCUGGGCCCACCCUAGCAGCCUGGUACUUUGGACAACCAAACAGAUGAACGAACGGAGCACAGCAGUGCUAUGAAAGUUACUGUAAGCCUGAAAUAAACUGUAUUUUUCUUAAAAAAAAAAAAACACACAAAAAAACACAAAAAACUGAGUAUCCAUUGUCCUCCCCCCUGUUUCCCUGUCCUGCCCGCUGGCCCUGCCAUGGGUCUGGACGAUAAAAUACUGGGUAGCCUUGGGGCCGGGUAGAAGCUGUAAGCCAUGGGAGAGGCAGGAGAGGUCUAGUUGCCACCCCACGUGGAGUUGUACGUGUGAAGACACUGGCUGAGGAGGCAGGGCUGGGUCGGGGCCCCAGGGUCAGUGGCAGAGCUGGCACUUGAAUCCAGGUCUCCUACCUCUGGUGCUUUGUGGGGAACUGGGUGGAGGCAGGAUCUGUGGUAGGGUAUUGAGGGAUGAGGGAGAAAAACGACCUAAUUCAGGUAGGACUGGCAACGGCUCCCACCCUCCCUGGGGACAGGGAUUAAUAAAAAUUGACAUCACUGUAGGAAUAUAUUUUUUAAAAGCCCACGUUUUGUGAAAAGAUGAAUUAAAAAACCCAAGACCCAGCAUUCGGGAUUGAAAGUGCCCGUGAUGGGAGUUCAAGUAUUGACUGAGCUGGGAGGGAAGGGGCUAGAGCCCCCAAUCAGACAUGGGCAACUAGAGUGUGGGGUGGGGGCUCCCAGUUUGUCCCAAACCCUCUAGGUCUUGUCUCGGGUCUGGGGGGAUUCGGGGGGUUCAGCAGUGGCUCCUAAAGCAGCCACCGGUGCCUCCUCCAUCUCCCUGUCCUCAGACAGUGUGGGCCCCGGGCAGAACGUGUCCCCUCGGCCCGCCCGGCCAAGCACAGCCAUCCAGCGUCGCUGUAGUUCCUCUGUCUCAGGGCUGAAGUACCAGCUGAGGUGGCUCUGGGUGAUCUUGAAGACAUGCCUUCUGUCAGGCCGCUCCCCUGCCUCGGGCGGUCCCACCUCGAAGCCAAUGAGGGGCAGGCUGCGCUGGGCUUUCACAUCCUGGCGGGAGGAGGGACAGAGCUGGGGCCACCUUGGGGCUAGACCUUUCCCCCGCCCCAGCUUCUAACUGGUUUUGCAUAUGCUCUGUCUUCAGUCCCCUACUCAGGAACUCCCCUACUCAGGAACCUUCCGUGGCUCCAGUGUUAUCAACAGGAACAUGUCAGAACUGGGGCUAAAAUGCAGGCUGGUUUAAAUACCUGUCUCCCCCCACCCCCGCCUCUUCUCACAAAACUGCUGGGCUAGUCUCUUUAGCAUACCAAAUAAUGUUUUCAGGCCUUUGUCUAUGCUAUUGCCCCUAUCUGCAUACUUUUUUUUUUUUUUUUUUUUGAGACAGAGUCUUGCCCUGUUGCCCAGGCUGGAGUGCAGUGGCAUGAACUUGGCUCACUGCAACCUCUACCUCCCAGGUUCAAGCAAUUCUCCUGCCUCAGCUUCCUGAGUAGCUGGGACUACAGGCACACGUCACCACGCCAGGCUAAUUUUUGUAUUUUUAGUAGAGACGGGGUUUCACCAUGUUGGCCAGGCUGGUCUUGAACUCCUGAUCUCAGGUGAGCCACCUGCCUCGGCCUCUCAGAGUGCUGGGAUUACAGGCGUGAGCCACUGCGCUCGGUCCCAUCUGCAUACUCUUACCCACUCCAAAUUGGACCUAGCAGUUCCCCAUCUCUACUCCUUCCAGGAAGCCAGGCCCACAACUCAUCCUGGUUUUCCCUACAUACCACAACCACUCCUUGUCUCUAGCCAGUCUUUGUCUCUCAAGGGUUGGGGUUCUGAUUUCCUCUUAGAGAUAGGCUCACCUUAUCUUCCAAGGCUCACCUUAUCUUCCAAGGCCAAGGAGAGGUCAAGGACUGGAUCUGGCUUUGCCAGGUGGCUGAAAGGACCCGAAGGAGUAGGAUGCAUACCUGAGGGGCUCCGUAGAUAUACAGCACCAAGGGUUCAUUUUCAGGGACCACGAACCAUGCCUUGUGCCAUCCUUUGCCACCCUUCUCCAUGUAGUGCAGGAAGCUGCAGAUGACGCUGUUCUCUGCAGCCACUGAGGCCUGUUUCUGUGGCCAGAGACACCGGGCAUCAAUGUUGACAGAAGGCCUAGCCUGGCUCCUCCUAGCUUUAAUACCUCCUCAGUGUAGGGACUGCUAUUCCUAUCUCAGAUGAAGACGCUCAAGCUCAGGUGGCAGGAGUGAUUUGUCCAGUGCCACCCAGUGAAUCAGCUAGAGCUGAGAUUCAAAGCUAGGUUCGUCUGCCUCAUUUGGGCAACGGCUGCUGCCUCUACAGGCCAGUGGAAGGAGUGUGCGGAUCUCAGGCAUUCUUUCUUCAGUCAGAGCAUUCAUUCCUCAAGCCAUUCACACAUUUAGGCCUCAUGCUUUUUUCUGUCUUUCAUCACAUCCAUUUCCUACACUCAUUGAGAGGUAAUCUAGCAUUGUGGUUUUAAGGGGGUAUGUGGGUGGUUAAUGAAGUCUGGCUUAGAAUCCCAGCUCUAGAUGAAAAUGUAUUGACUUGGAGAGCAAAGAGAGCUGAUGUGAGAAUUAAAUGAAUUAAUAUAUGCAAAGUGCUUAGAAUAGUUCCUGGCACAGAGUAAGUACUCUUUUAAGUGUUAAAUAAAUACCUAGAUUUGUUUUUAAAAAAA